AGGAGCGGGCCCCCGGAGGCCGAGGGGUUCGGCGACGCGGAGGGAGGGAGAGUCUGGGCCGCGCGGGAGCCGCAGGGCGCCCUAGCCUUCGCAGAAACGAUGGCGGAGGAAGAAGGUGAUUGCCGCGGGGUCCAGCGCGCCAACGGCUGCCAGUGGUCUCGGGAAGGAGGGGCGGGGGCGCUGGAGGUCUGGGUUGGAGCUGCUGGUGGCCGCGGUCGCGGUGGCGGCCGCGCGGGCAGGGCGGGAAGGAGCGCGGCGCCCAGGAGAGGACUGCGGAGAAAUUCAGGAGAGCGGAGCAAAUGGCCCGAAGUUUUGUCGGCCGAAUUGGGAAGCAAAGGACCACCUGUAGAGCUGCGCCAAAGAAAAAAGCCAAAGUCUUCAGAAAAUAAGGAAUCUGCCAAAGAAGAGAAAAUCAGUGACAUUCCAAUUCCUGAAAGAGCUCCAAAACAUGUAUUAUUUCAACGCUUUGCAAAGAUUUUCAUUGGCUGUCUUGCAGCGGUUACUAGUGGUAUGAUGUAUGCUCUCUACUUAUCAGCAUACCAUGAACGGAAAUUCUGGUUUUCCAACAGGCAGGAGCUUGAACGGGAAAUCACGUUUCAGGGUGACAGUGCCAUUUAUUACUCCUAUUAUAAAGAUAUGUUAAAGGCACCUUCAUUUGAAAGAGGUGUUUACGAACUGACACACAAUAACAAAACUGUAUCUCUGAAGACUAUAAAUGCAGUGCAGCAAAUGUCUCUGUAUCCGGAACUUAUUGCUAGCAUUUUAUAUCAAGCCACUGGUAGCAAUGAGAUUAUUGAGCCAGUGUAUUUCUAUAUUGGCAUUGUUUUUGGAUUGCAAGGAAUAUAUGUUACUGCUUUAUUUGUUACAAGUUGGCUUAUGAGUGGAACAUGGCUAGCAGGAAUGCUUACUGUUGCGUGGUUCGUUAUUAACAGGGUAGAUACAACAAGAAUUGAAUACUCCAUUCCUUUAAGAGAAAACUGGGCACUACCAUAUUUUGCAUGCCAAAUUGCUGCACUUACAGGCUAUUUAAAAAGCAACUUAAAUACUUAUGGAGAGAGGUUUUGCUACUUGUUGAUGAGUGCUUCAACUUACACAUUUAUGAUGAUGUGGGAGUAUAGCCACUAUCUCCUGUUUCUUCAAGCAAUAUCUCUAUUCCUGCUAGAUACCUUUUCAGUGGAGCAAAGUGACAAGGUUUAUGAAGUUUAUAAAAUCUACAUAUUUUCCCUCUUUCUGGGAUAUUUACUACAGUUUGAGAAUCCAGCUUUGUUGGUAUCUCCUUUAUUAAGUUUAGUAGCAGCCUUAAUGCUUGCUAAGUGCCUUCAGCUGAAUGUGAAGAAAGGAAGUUUUGUAGCUAAAAUAAUAAAAGUGAUUAAUUUUUACUUGGUGUGUACUCUGACAAUAACAUUGAAUAUUAUAAUGAAGAUGUUUGUCCCACACAAAGAAAAUGGGCACAUGCUGAAAUUCCUUGAAGUAAAAUUUGGACUAAAUAUGACCAAGAAUUUUACAAUGAAUUGGCUCCUCUGUCAAGAAUCCCUGCAGGCACCAUCUCAAGAUUUUUUUCUGCGAUUGACACAGUCUUCUUUAUUACCUUUCUACAUUCUAGUGUUAAUUAUUUGUUUUCUUUCUAUGUUGCAAGUUAUUUUUAGGAGGAUUAAUGGUAAGUCCCUGAAGGAAACUGUUACUCUUGAAGAUGGACGAAUUGGAGAAAGACCAGAAAUAAUUUAUCAUGUAAUUCACACUAUUUUAUUGGGUUCUCUUGCAAUGGUUAUAGAAGGCUUGAAGUACAUCUGGAUUCCUUAUGUGUGCAUGUUAGCAGCAUUUGGUGUAUGUUCUCCCGAACUUUGGAUGACACUUUUCAAGUGGCUUCGAUUAAGAACUGUACACCCAAUAUUGUUGGCUCUUAUUCUGAGCAUGGCCGUGCCUACUAUAAUAGGUCUCAGCUUAUGGAAAGAGUUUUUUCCCAGAUUAAUGACAGAAUUAAUGGAACUACAGGAAUUCUAUGACCCAGAUACAGUGGAACUUAUGACCUGGAUAAAAAGGCAAGCUCCAGUUGCAGCUGUGUUUGCAGGGAGUCCACAGUUAAUGGGUGCGAUUAAAUUAUGCACUGGAUGGAUGGUGACAAGUUUGCCUCUUUACAAUGAUGAUGAUCUUCUCAAGAGAAAUGAAAAUAUCUACCAAAUCUAUUCAAAGCGAUCUGCUGAGGAUAUUUAUAAAAUACUGACAUCUUACAAAGCUAAUUACCUAAUUGUAGAGGAUGCUAUCUGCAAUGAGGUGGGACCCAUGAGAGGCUGUAGGGUUAAAGAUUUAUUAGACAUUGCAAAUGGCCACAUGGUUUGUGAAGAAGGUGACAAGCUAACCUACUCAAAAUAUGGGCGAUUUUGUCAUGAGGUCAAAAUUAACUAUUCUCCAUAUGUGAAUUAUUUCACUAGAGUAUACUGGAACAGAUCCUACUUUGUAUAUAAAAUCAACACUGUGAUAUCCUUCCAGUCUUGAAAAAUAACAGAGCCUUCAUUUCAAAGACUACCUGAAGUAAAAUGCAGUUUUCUUCUACCUACUCGGUGUCUUUUGCAGAUCAGAGUAUGGACAUUUGAAAUAUUGCUGCUUCUUUCCCCCUUCUGCUGUUAACUGGAUCCAGAGUUCUGUGGGAAAUAGAAGAUCAAGCAUUACUGUCCUUUGAUUAAAUGUGAUAUCUACCACUCUGCAAUAUUCCAGACAGGUGUCUUCCUUACCGUUACAUGGUCUUUAACACUUUUACUGAUUGCAAUAUUUUCCCCAUAAAAUCUUCAUUCUAUUAUAAUAUUGAUCUUGAAUUUGAAUAUGUGCAAGGUCAGAUACAUUUCUCAAACAUAACAUUUAAUAAAUAAUGUGAUAUAAUUAUUUAAUAGAAAGAAUAAUUCCGACCUUCAAGCAAGUUUCUGAAGGUAUUUUAUGAUGUAUAACAACUGAAGUUUUACAAUAAAAACUAAUUUAAAUGUUAGCUGAAGAUAUGUGGCAUUUAAAUUAAAAUGGAAAUUAUAUAAAGGAAAGUGAUUUUUAAGGAUAUACAUAAAGAUAUAUUUAGAAUUUUCAUGAUACUGUUCUCCUCAUCUACUGCUUAUGUUAAGUGAGAACUUUCUUAGUAAUACAUAAUGCAUGAUGUUACUGCAUUUUCUAAAUGACUAGUAAGUGAUUAGUUUUUUCACUUAUGCCUAUUAAUUUGAUACCAAUUUAAUCAUGAUAAAACAAUAACCGUUAACAUAUAUUUUGUUAAAUGGACAUUUAAAAGAAUGUUGUUCAGGUUUUUUUUUUAAAUACUGAUAUGGGGCAUACAAUCUAUUCACAUGUUUUCUACUGAAGUACUAAGUAAAAAAAUUAAAUCAUUAUCAGAAUAAAAAUAUGUGUUCUAAAAUUAGCAACAAUUUCUGGGGAUACAUGCAGAUGUUGUUAAACGUACCUCUGCAUACAGAUAUAUUAUAAAACACAAGCAAUGUUAUUUAUGAAACUGUGAUGCAGUCUUCAACAUCAAGAAAAAAUGACAACUAUAAUAAAAUUUACAACACAGUUUCACAGUCUAAAUGCUAUGUUCCUUUAAGUAUUUUCAUAUUUUUAAUCAUUUAUUAAGAGAAAAUUGUGAAAAGUUAAUUUGGCCUUAUAGAGAGAUUCAGGAUAGAUGUAGCCUAUAGAUGUGUCAUUUUAAUAAGUUGGGAUACAUGUUUAGUUUUUCCUUAUAUUCCUGUUCAGUGAACAGAUUUUCAUAAUUCUCACUUGUUAAAGUGCUGCAAAAAUUGCAUUUUCAGUACUCUAAAUUACUACAUUAGAAGAGAGCAUUUCUCCAUUGUCUUUAUUUUCUGUUAUAUAUGUGUUGUAAAAGUACACUACAUUAGAAGGGAGCUUUUCCGUUGUCUUUAUUUUCUGUUAUACAUGUGUUGUUAAAGUACAUGCAUUCUUAGACUAACUCUCAGAUGCUUUGCUCUUUUGGAGCUGAAGAAUUGUUUGAUGGUGAUGUCAUAUAUCUGAUAGAUUAGUUUCAGUGGUUCUCAUUUCACUUUUAUACGUAAUUUCUUAACUAUAUUAAGAUAGUUGCAGGCAGUGUACCUCAGGUUGACUCUGUACAUCUGAAUAGUGAGUCACUAGUAUUUUGCUUCAAGCCUUCUGAAAAUAUAACCAUAGUUACCUAAGCACACAGUGAAUAGUCACAUGGUAGUACUUGUGAUUAGAGCAUGUAAAACAAUGUAAUUGAAAAGUCAGCUUCCAUAUUUUGUAGGGGAAAUAGAACACCCUACUUUUUAUCUAGUGUGAAAUAUUUAAUCGAAUUUUUGUUGAUUUAUAUUAUGUUACCUGUGCUGAAUUAGGUUUGGUACUUGUGUUUUGUUUGACAUAUUAGUAAGUUGCUUUUGCUUCUUUCUGUCAACUUAUUUUUUAAAUAAAAUUGAUCUGGAAAAAUUGUUAAUGGGAUGUUUUAAAUAAUGAAUUUUUCAUCCAGCAUCAGUUGAAAAGGAAAAGAAAGCUUCAUUAUGGAAAUGACAAUAUUGAAUAUGACAGAUAAGUUUAUUUGCUUCUGUUUUAACUGCAGUUAAUAGUACUAGACAACUUUAAGUGGAAAGCAUUUAGUUUAUUUCUUCACUUAUUUGUAGAGUGAACAAAUGAUUCACAAUUCUACAAGUAAUUCCACUUAGGUAACUUACAGUUGUUAGGUUUGACAAUAAAGAUCUACUAUGAGAGGAGAAGAAUUUAUGGGUUUUGGGUGGAAGGAAUUUCUCAAAGAAAUAAAAAAUGUUCUUUGCCCUUGAUACUGCAAACCCACUGAUACAAGUGCCUUGAAUUUAUUAUUAUUAUUAUUUUUUAUUUUUUUGAGAUGGAGUUUCACUCUUGUCUCCCAGGCUGGAGUGCAAUGGCGCGAUCUUGGCUCACUGCAACCUCCGCUCGCUGCAACCUCCGCCUCCCAGGUUCAAGUGAUUCUCCUGCCUCAGCCUCCGGAGUAGCUGGGAUUACAGGCACCUGCCACCAAGCACGGCUAAUUUUUGUAUUUUUAGUAGAAACGGGGUUUCGCCAUGUUGGCCAGGCUGGUCUCGAACUCCUGACCUCAGAUGAUCCACUCACCCCAGCCUCCCAAAGUGCUGGGAUUACAGACGUGAGCCACUGCGCCCGGCGCAAGUCUUUGUUAAAAGUAGAGAUGGAGGCCAGGCGCAGUGGCUCACUCCUGUAAUCCCAGCACUUUGGGAGGCUGAGGCAGGCAGAUCACGAGGUCAGGAGAUCGAGACCAUCUUGGCUAACACGGUGAAACCCCGUCUCUACUGAAAAUACAAAAAAUUAGCCGGGCAGGGUGGCGGGCGCCUGUAGUCCCAGCUACUCCGAGGCUGAAGCAGGAGAAUGGCGUCAAGCGGCGAGGCGGAGCUUGCGGUGAGCCGAGAUCAUGCCGCUGCACUCCAGCCUGGGCAACAGAGCAAGACUCCAUCUCAAAAAGAAAAAAAAAGUAGAGAUGGGAUCUCUAGCCUCCUAAGUUAAUUUAGCCUCCCAAAUGCCAGACAAAGAAUCUAACAUAAAAUUUACCUUGAAUAAGAUAUAUGAUAUUGAUUCUGAGCUGCUUUGUAUUUUUUCUGACUUUGGCAUCUGUAUCUUGGUGCUUUCUGUUAGACUGGUAGAGUUUAAGAACCUAAGGAGUAUGCAUUGUACUUCAGUGCUAACUUUUUUCUUCAUUUACUUUCUGUGUAUAUAGGCAGCAUAUUUUUUUUGUAGAACAUUAACCCAGAUUGCUAAUAGCUUCAUGUUACGGCAUUCUUCCACACAGUCCAGAUUGAUUUAAGGAAAAGCAGAAAUGGAAGUCAAAGUGUGUUAUAAAUUGAGACUGAAAAACAUGCUUUAAAAAAUAGAUUUAAUUUCUUACACUGUGAAUAGCCAUUGUAUUGUUUUGUUUCUGAUAAAUCAGUUGUUUUGGGCCCCUAUUUUUGAACUGUUAAAAAAUUUUGAUGCUUUUCGUGGAUAAAAGUAGUGCCUCUCUUUAUACAACUGAUGGGGUUUUAAAAAGUGUAAAUUGCCUUUUUUGUUAAACUUAUUUUAAAUGCUUUAGUAUUUAAAGGGUGUAUGUUAUUAAUUAAUCUGCAUAUUUGUAACGCAAAUAACUACUUCCUGAUUUACAUCUCAAUAUAUUCUUCUUUCAUUUGCCCAAUUUAAAAAAUACGUAGUCUCUAUUGUUGCUGUUUACUAAUAGUUUUAGAUCCCAAUGUGUAUUAGAAUUAUAGCUACAAAAAGUUGCAAGUAAAAUUUAGCAAUUUCCUAUUCAAACAGGAUCUCAUUAGUAUGUUUUUUAAUGUGUAGAAUUAACACUUUAAAAUAAACAGGUGUGAAAAUUAUAAAGGAAUAUAUAUGACAAUUAUUUUCUGUACAUUAAUGUCUAAACAUUAUACUUACUUUUUCAUAAUAAAGGAAAUUUUGGAACCAAA